GGAAGGAACCGAGCCCGUCCGAAGGGAGCGGAGCGCAGCCUGGCCUGGGGCCCGGUCGAGCCCGCGCCAUGGCGGCCGAGGCGACAGCUGUGGCCGGAAGCGGGGCUGUUGGCGGCUGCCUGGCCAAAGACGGCUUGCAGCAGUCUAAGUGCCCGGACACUACCCCAAAACGGCGGCGCGCCUCGUCGCUGUCGCGUGACGCCGAGCGCCGAGCCUACCAAUGGUGCCGGGAGUACUUGGGCGGGGCCUGGCGCCGAGUGCAGCCCGAGGAGCUGAGGGUUUACCCCGUGAGCGGAGGCCUCAGCAACCUGCUCUUCCGCUGCUCGCUCCCGGACCACCUGCCCAGCGUUGGCGAGGAGCCCCGGGAGGUGCUUCUGCGGCUGUACGGAGCCAUCUUGCAGGGCGUGGACUCCCUGGUGCUAGAAAGCGUGAUGUUCGCCAUACUUGCGGAGCGGUCGCUGGGGCCCCAGCUGUACGGAGUCUUCCCAGAGGGCCGGCUGGAACAGUACAUCCCAAGUCGGCCAUUGAAAACUCAAGAGCUUCGAGAGCCAGUGUUGUCAGCAGCCAUUGCCACGAAGAUGGCGCAAUUUCAUGGCAUGGAGAUGCCUUUCACCAAGGAGCCCCACUGGCUGUUUGGGACCAUGGAGCGGUACCUAAAACAGAUCCAGGACCUGCCCCCAACUGGCCUCCCUGAGAUGAACCUGCUGGAGAUGUACAGCCUGAAGGAUGAGAUGGGCAACCUCAGGAAGUUACUAGAGUCUACCCCAUCGCCAGUCGUCUUCUGCCACAAUGACAUCCAGGAAGGGAACAUCUUGCUGCUCUCAGAGCCAGAAAAUGCUGACAGCCUCAUGCUGGUGGACUUCGAGUACAGCAGUUAUAACUAUAGGGGCUUUGACAUUGGGAACCAUUUUUGUGAGUGGGUUUAUGAUUAUACUCACGAGGAAUGGCCUUUCUACAAAGCAAGGCCCACAGACUACCCCACUCAAGAACAGCAGUUGCAUUUUAUUCGUCAUUACCUGGCAGAGGCAAAGAAAGGUGAGACCCUCUCCCAAGAGGAGCAGAGAAAACUGGAAGAAGAUUUGCUGGUAGAAGUCAGUCGGUAUGCUCUGGCAUCCCAUUUCUUCUGGGGUCUGUGGUCCAUCCUCCAGGCAUCCAUGUCCACCAUAGAAUUUGGUUACUUGGACUAUGCCCAGUCUCGGUUCCAGUUCUACUUCCAGCAGAAGGGGCAGCUGACCAGUGUCCACUCCUCAUCCUGACUCCACCCUCCCACUCCUUGGAUUUCUCCUGGAGCCUCCAGGGCAGGACCUUGGAGGGAGGAACAACGAGCAGAAGGCCCUGGCGACUGGGCUGAGCCCCCAAGUGAAACUGAGGUUCAGGAGACCGGCCUGUUCCUGAGUUUGAGUAGGUCCCCAUGGCUGGCAGGCCAGAGCCCCGUGCUGUGUAUGUAACACAAUAAACAAGCUUCUUCUUCCCA